GGCUCGGUAAAGAUGGCGGCGCCCAGGGCGGUAGCGUGAAACUUGGUGGAAGACGCUGACCAGUCGUGUUGGAAUCAAAACAGCGGGGACCCUGCGCCAUGUCGCGACUGAUCGUGAAGAAUCUCCCGAAUGGGAUGAAGGAGGAGCGUUUCAGGCAGCUGUUUGCCGCCUUCGGCACGCUGACAGACUGCAGCCUGAAGUUCACCAAAGAUGGCAAGUUCCGCAAGUUUGGUUUUAUUGGCUUCAAGUCCGAGGAAGAGGCCCAGAAGGCACAGAAGCAUUUCAACAAGAGCUUCAUCGACACAUCCCGGAUCACAGUGGAGUUCUGCAAGUCAUUCGGGGACCCGGCCAAACCCAGAGCCUGGAGCAAACAUGCCCAGAAACCAAGCCAGCCCAAGCAGCCUCCAAAAGACUCUACUACUCCAGAAAUUAAGAAAGAUGAGAAGAAGAAAAAGGUGGCAGGUCAACUGGAGAAGCUGAAGGAGGAUACAGAGUUCCAGGAGUUUCUGUCAGUUCAUCAGAGGCGGGCGCAGGCAGCCACUUGGGCGAAUGAUGGCCUGGAUGCUGAGCCCUCGAAAGGGAAGAGCAAGCCGGCCAGUGACUACCUGAACUUCGACUCCGAUUCUGGGCAGGAGAGUGAGGAGGAGGGAGCCGGGGAGGACCUGGAAGAAGAGGCAAGCCUCGAACCAAAGGCAGCUGUGCAGAAGGAGCUGUCGGACAUGGAUUACCUGAAAUCCAAGAUGGUGAAGGCUGGGUCGUCCUCUUCCUCGGAGGAAGAGGAAAGUGAAGAUGAAGCCGUGCACUGUGAUGAAGGGAGUGAGGCCGAGGAAGAGGAUUCCUCCGCCACCCCAGUCCUGCAGGAAAGAGACAGCAAGGGUGCAGGCCAAGAGCAAGGGAUGCCAGCUGGGAAAAAGAGACCACCGGAGGCCAGAGCCGAGACAGAGAAACCAGCAAACCAGAAGGAACCCACCACCUGCCACACCGUGAAGCUGCGGGGAGCCCCGUUCAAUGUCACAGAGAAAAAUGUUAUGGAAUUCCUGGCACCCCUGAAACCAGUGGCCAUUCGAAUUGUGAGAAACGCUCAUGGGAAUAAAACAGGAUACAUCUUUGUGGAUUUCAGCAAUGAAGAGGAAGUGAAGCAAGCUCUGAAAUGCAACCGGGAGUACAUGGGUGGGCGCUACAUCGAGGUGUUCAGGGAAAAGAACGUCCCCACCACCAAGGGUGCACCAAAGAAUACCACCAAAUCCUGGCAAGGCCGGAUACUCGGGGAGAACGAAGAGGAGGAGGACCUGGCCGAAUCCGGAAGGCUCUUUGUACGGAACCUGCCCUACACCAGCACCGAGGAGGAUCUGGAGAAGCUCUUCUCCAAAUAUGGUCCCCUGUCUGAGCUCCACUACCCCAUCGACAGCCUGACCAAGAAACCCAAGGGUUUUGCAUUCAUCACCUUCAUGUUCCCUGAGCACGCUGUGAAGGCCUACUCGGAGGUGGACGGGCAGGUAUUCCAGGGCAGGAUGCUCCACGUGUUACCAUCUACCAUCAAGAAGGAAGCCAGCGAGGAUGCCAGUGCCCUGGGAUCGUCGUCCUACAAGAAGAAGAAGGAGGCCCAGGACAAAGCCAACAGUGCCAGCUCUCACAACUGGAACACACUAUUCAUGGGGCCGAAUGCCGUGGCCGAUGCCAUCGCACAGAAGUACAACGCCACCAAGAGUCAAGUGUUUGACCACGAGACCAAGGGCAGCGUGGCCGUGCGCGUGGCUCUGGGGGAAACCCAGCUCGUCCAGGAAGUGCGGCGUUUUCUCAUAGACAACGGGGUCAGCCUGGAUUCCUUCAGCCAGGCUGCAGCAGAGCGAAGCAAGACUGUGAUUCUGGUCAAGAACCUCCCGGCAGGCACCCUGGCGGCCCAGCUGCAGGAGACCUUCGGCCAUUUUGGCAGCCUGGGCCGCGUGCUGCUGCCAGAGGGCGGAAUCACUGCCAUCGUGGAGUUCCUGGAGCCCCUGGAGGCCCGCAAGGCCUUCAGGCAUCUGGCCUAUUCCAAGUUCCAUCAUGUCCCCCUCUAUCUGGAGUGGGCUCCAGUUGGCGUCUUCUCCAGCACAGCCCCACAGAAGAAAAAGCUCCAAGACACACCUUCAGAACCCAUGGAAAAGGACCCAGCAGAGCCAGAAACAGUGCCUGAUGGCGAAACCCCAGAAGAUGAAAAUCCAACAGAGGAAGGAGCAGACAACUCUUCAGCAAAGAUGGAAGAGGAGGAGGAGGAAGAGGAAGAAGAAGAAGAGAGCCUCCCAGGAUGUACUCUGUUUAUUAAGAAUCUCAAUUUUGACACAACAGAAGAGAAGCUGAAGGAAGUGUUUUCAAAAGUGGGGACAGUGAAGAGCUGCUCCAUCUCCAAGAAGAAGAACAAAGCAGGAGUGCUCCUUUCCAUGGGGUUUGGAUUUGUGGAAUACAGGAAGCCGGAGCAAGCCCAGAAAGCUCUCAAGCAGCUCCAGGGUCACGUCGUGGACGGCCACAAGCUGGAAGUGAGGAUCUCGGAACGAGCCACUAAGCCAGCCGUGACAUUGGCUCGGAAGAAACAAGUUCCCAGAAAGCAGACCACCUCCAAGAUCCUGGUGCGGAACAUCCCCUUCCAGGCCCACAGCCGGGAGAUCCGAGAGCUCUUCAGCACCUUUGGGGAGUUGAAGACGGUCCGCCUGCCAAAGAAGAUGACUGGGACAGGCACACACAGAGGCUUCGGCUUUGUGGACUUCCUCACCAAGCAGGAUGCGAAGAGAGCCUUCAACGCCCUGUGUCACAGCACCCACUUGUACGGGCGGAGGCUGGUGCUGGAGUGGGCCGACUCCGAGGUGACCCUGCAGGCCCUGCGGCGGAAGACGGCCGCUCACUUUCACGAGCCCCCGAAGAAAAAGCGGUCUGUGGUGUUGGACGAGAUCCUGGAGCAGCUGGAAGGCAGUGACAGCGACAGCGAGGAGCAGACCCUUCAGCUGUGAGCUGGCACCGAGAGGGCUGGAGUGCAGUGGCGUGAUCUGGGCUCACCUCCCUGGUUCAAGCGAUUGUCCCGCCUCAGCCUCCCAAGGCUGGGAUUACAGGUAUGCACCACCACGCCCGGCUAAUUUUGUAUUUUUCAUAGAGACUGGGUUUCACCAUGUAGACCAGGCUGGUCUCGAAUUCCUGACCUCAAGUGAUCCACCUACCUCGGCCUCCCAAAGUGUGGGGAUUACGGGUGUGAGCCACCACGCCCGGCUAAUUUUUUGUAUUUUUAGUAGACAGGGUUUCACCAUGUGGGCCAGGCUGGUCUUGAACUCCCAACCUCAAGUGAUCCACCCACCUUGUUCUCCCAAAGUGCUGAGAUUACAGGUGUGAGCCACCAUGCCCAGCCUGUUCCUAACCCUUUCAACUGGGGGGUCUCAAGUGGGUGAGGACUCCAUGGCCACGGCAGCAGAACUGUCUCUUCUGAAAACCAGACUCCGGGGCCCCUGGGUCAGCACCUCUAGGUCAUUCCACAGACUUACACAGUUUAAAGAAAGAGCCAGCGAACAUGGGGUGAUCCUGGGGUGCCACUGGGAUCCCAAGCCAGGCCCGGAGGUCUGCCUGUUUCGUCCCCAGAAACUUGAGCUGGCAUCCUCCGCUGGUUUGCACUGGGCACGGGGACUGGAGAGCCACCAGGCCACUGAGCGCAGCAUGCUAUCACUUCUCAGGAAGUUGUGAGGGUGAGGAGAAUAGCCGGGCCCACUCUGCAGAGGGGAGGAACAGGCACAGGCUAGAGGCACGGGCUGAUAGAGUGAGUCCUCUCCCUCAUUCAUUCAUUCAUUCAUUCAUUCAUCCAUCAGACACCUGCUGGGCAUCUGCUGUGUGCGAGACACUGUGCUGGGUGCCCCAGACACAAGACAGAAACUCGGGUCGCUCUGUGUGCCUCCACACUGGCCUUCCCUGCUGCGUGGACGCAGGCUCUGUCUCCUAGGCUUUAAGCCCCAUGCAUCAGGUGGAAGACAAUUUCCAGCAGCCUCUGCCCGCUUGUUUUUCCUCCUCUCCUUUUCCUGCCGCCUUGGUCUUUUUUGUCUUUUGUGCAGGGCCGUCUCUCGCAGCGCCCGUCUGUGCUCCGCAGCGUCUAGGAAAGGAUUAGUGUGAGCAGAGCACGCAGGCUUUGGUGAACAGAGCCGAGCUUGGUUUCAACAUCUAAUUCAAUUUGUUCUGCCGAGAUUGAAAUAUGAAAUGGUUGCCAGUCAAACGUUCAAAGGACGGGGAAGGGAGAGUGAGCGCAUGCUGAAAUUUAAAUUUUAAUGAAAAUGACUUUAACCCUUUGGUACACCUUGCAAAAUGUAACCCAUCCUCCCAUCCUGUGAAAGCGGCCUCUCGGGUUAGAGCUUUUCCACCCACUUCUCUUCCACUGAGCUUCACUAAUAAUAUGUAAUCAUUUUUUUCAGCCGUCUUAAUAAUAAAAGAUUAAUAGAA